AAACAAGUGCGCUCCCUACUGCAGUCACCAGGAGGCGCUAGUCCCGCCUGUCUCCCGGCACGGGUCCUCGUUUGCGCACGCGUCAUUUCUUUCCUCCAGCGUCCCCGCCCCUUCUCCUCCGGCCGCCACCAGUUUCGCUUGGCCAGUUGCGUUCGUGCGGCGACGUCCACGCAUUUUCUGACGUAGCGAGCGACGGCGGGGAGCCGAGCGGAAGUCCAGCACUAUUGCCGCUAGAGGAGGGGAGGGGUGAGAAGCAUAAGUGGCACCGGAAGUGGAAUUAAUCCGCCUACCUCUCCUGCGCCUGCGAAACAGAAAAGACAAGGCGCCUGUCGGGCGGGGUGUGGCUUCGGGUGGCGGAGAACGCUGCGAUUGGCCCUCGGCUGUGGCGACAGCGACGAUUGGUCCCUGCGUGCAGAGCGCGAGGUCCCCCCUAUUGGAAGUAAAGGGGAACAUAGAACUGAAGAGACCUCUGAUUAAGGCCCCUUCCCAGCUGCCUCUCUCAGGAAGCAGACUCAAGAGGAGGCCUGACCAGAUGGAAGAUGGCCUGGAGCCUGAGAAGAAACGGACAAGAGGCCUGGGUGCAACGACCAAAAUUACCACAUCCCACCCAAGAGUUCCAUCCCUCACUACAGUGCCACAGACACAAGGCCAGACCACAGCUCAAAAAGUUUCCAAGAAGACAGGACCCCGGUGUUCCACAGCUAUUGCCACAGGGUUGAAGAACCAGAAGCCAGUUCCUGCUGUUCCUGUCCAGAAGUCUGGCACAUCAGGUGUUCCUCCCAUGGCAGGAGGGAAGAAACCCAGCAAACGUCCAGCCUGGGACUUAAAGGGUCAGUUAUGUGACCUAAAUGCAGAACUAAAACGGUGCCGUGAGAGGACUCAAACGUUGGACCAAGAGAACCAGCAGCUUCAGGACCAGCUCAGAGAUGCCCAGCAGCAGGUCAAGGCCCUGGGGACAGAGCGCACAACACUGGAGGGGCAUUUAGCCAAGGUACAGGCCCAGGCUGAGCAGGGCCAACAGGAGCUGAAGAACUUGCGUGCUUGUGUCCUGGAGCUGGAAGAGCGGCUGAGCACGCAGGAGGGCUUGGUGCAAGAGCUUCAGAAAAAACAGGUGGAAUUGCAGGAAGAACGGAGGGGACUGAUGUCCCAACUAGAGGAGAAGGAGAGGAGGCUGCAGACAUCAGAAGCAGCCCUGUCAAGCAGCCAAGCAGAGGUGGCAUCUCUGCGGCAGGAGACUGUGGCCCAGGCAGCCUUACUGACUGAGCGGGAAGAACGUCUUCAUGGGCUAGAAAUGGAGCGCCGGCGACUGCACAACCAGCUGCAGGAACUCAAGGGCAACAUCCGUGUAUUCUGCCGGGUCCGCCCUGUCCUGCCGGGGGAGCCCACUCCACCCCCUGGCCUCCUCCUGUUUCCCUCUGGCCCUGGUGGGCCCUCUGAUCCUCCAACCCGCCUUAGCCUCUCCCGGUCUGACGAGCGGCGUGGGACCCUGAGUGGGGCACCAGCUCCCCCAACUCGCCAUGAUUUUUCCUUUGACCGGGUAUUCCCACCAGGAAGUGGACAGGAUGAAGUGUUUGAAGAGAUUGCCAUGCUUGUCCAGUCAGCCCUGGAUGGCUAUCCAGUAUGCAUCUUUGCCUAUGGCCAGACAGGCAGUGGCAAGACCUUCACAAUGGAGGGUGGGCCUGGGGGAGACCCCCAGUUGGAGGGGCUGAUCCCUCGGGCCCUGCGGCACCUCUUCUCUGUGGCUCAGGAGCUGAGUGGUCAGGGCUGGACCUACAGCUUUGUAGCAAGCUACGUAGAGAUCUACAAUGAGACUGUCCGGGACCUGCUGGCCACUGGAACCCGGAAGGGUCAAGGGGGCGAGUGUGAGAUUCGCCGUGCAGGGCCAGGGAGUGAGGAGCUCACUGUCACCAAUGCUCGAUAUGUCCCUGUCUCCUGUGAGAAAGAAGUGGACGCCCUGCUUCAUCUGGCCCGCCAGAAUCGGGCUGUGGCCCGCACAGCCCAGAAUGAACGGUCAUCACGCAGCCACAGUGUAUUCCAGCUACAGAUUUCUGGGGAGCACUCCAGCCGAGGCCUGCAGUGUGGGGCCCCCCUCAGUCUUGUGGACCUGGCCGGGAGUGAGCGACUUGACCCCGGCUUAGCCCUCGGCCCCGGGGAGCGGGAACGCCUUCGGGAAACACAGGCCAUUAACAGCAGCCUGUCCACGCUGGGGCUGGUUAUCAUGGCCCUGAGCAACAAGGAGUCCCACGUGCCUUACCGGAACAGCAAACUGACCUACCUGCUGCAGAACUCUCUGGGUGGUAGUGCUAAGAUGCUCAUGUUUGUGAACAUUUCUCCACUGGAAGAGAACGUCUCCGAGUCCCUCAACUCUCUACGCUUUGCCUCCAAGGUGCGAUUACCACCCGUCAGCCUUGUCAGGACCCGUGGGUGGUUGUAGGCUUCUCCAUUCCAAUCCCUUUUGUCUUCUAGGGCAGGGAGCACAUUUGUGCAGAAAGGUUUUGCAGGUAUCUGAGGCACUGCUCACCUGGUUCCAUUUUUAAUUAUUAGCUUUUGAGUUAAAUUUUUUAAAAAACGGGUGAUUAAUUUAACCUGAGAAAGCUGAUUAAAAAAAAAAGAAAAGGUGACUAAAAGGUCUAAACUGGUUGGGCGCAGUAGCUCAUGCCUAUAAUCCGAACACUUCGGGAGGCCAAGGCAGGAGGAUUGCUUGAGCCCAGGAGUUUAAAAUCAGUCUGGGCAACAUAGUGAGACCCUGUCUCUACAAAAAAUAGGAAAAUUAGCUGGGUGUAAUGGCUCACACCUGUAGUUCCAGCUACUCAGGAGGCUGAGGUGGGAGGAUCACCUGAACCUGGGAGGUGGAGGCUGCAGUGAGCCGUGAUCCUACCACUGCACUUCAGCCUGGGUGACAGAGUAAGACCUUGUCUCAAAAAACCAACACACAAAAAAUCCCUAAGAUUCCUCCCUAUCAGCAUACAGAGAUCAUUAUUUUUAGGUCUGCCUAGACUCCACUAUGUAGCUGCACCAAAAUUUAUCCACCAGUUCCCUCUACUGGACACUUGGAUUGUUUCCACACUUUUUUAGUCACAAACAAGGCCACGUUGACUAACUUUGUACAUACAUCAUUUUGUAUUUUUCAGUUACAUCUAACUAGGGAAAUAGUCCUUGAAAUGGGAUUACUGGAUCAAAGACUUAGAGGUUUUUCAGACUAUUCCAAAUAGUGUGAAUUCAGACUCCAAACCUCAUGAGGGUCAGCCAGUGGCUAUAUGAAUUCUCACUAAUGAGAAUUCCUUCCACUAGAAUCUCCUUCCACUAGUGUUAAGCAAGUCAGAAAGUUUCCUUACUGUCUGCCUCCACAGUAAUUUUUUUCUCUGGUACACCCUCCUCCUGCGCGUAUAGCCCUUUGAUGGGCUCUGGCUUUAUUUGAGGUCUGAUCAGGUCUGUCCUGCUGUGCGCUUGGGCCUCCUCCCAGUCAGCACUGAUUGUUGCUGUGGAGUAGCCAGCACCUGCACCCUGAUCUGGUAUUCUACUUUGAUGAGGGUUUCCCUCACUAUCUUGCAAGUUCAAUUUUAGAGGGUGGUGAUGUUUUUUCUAACUUUUUAUUAAUGUUAUACCAAUGUAACAUCCAACAACAUGAACUUUAAUAUCCUCUAAUACCCAGUUUAUGUUAAAUUUCACCCAACUGUCUCAGAAGUGUCUUUUAUACAUAAUAGGUUUGUUCAAAUCAGGAUCCAGGCAAGGGCCACCCACUUGGUUGAAAUGUCUCAAGUUCCACAACCCUAUCCCACACUGCCACUAUUAUGUCGUUUGUUGAAGGUCAUUUGUCCUAUAGAAUAUACUAUUCUGGAUUUUGGCUGGUUGCUUCCUCUUUCCCCCAUACUUUCACUUAUUUAUCAUAUUUGGGUGUUGUCAACCUGACCCAUCCAUUUACAAGCUCCUUAUUGACUUUUUCACCUAGUGAUUUUAUCCAGCAGUGACCAUACCUGGAUCUUUAUUUCAUUAAGGGGUUUCUAAAUGGGGAUUUUUCUAAUCUUAGUUGUUCUGCAUUGGUUAGUCACGAUUCUUUUAUGAAGACAUUUGCCUUGCCAUCUACUUGGUUUCUCUGAAAUUCAAUUCAUACAGGAAAAACAAGAUAAAUGCUGAAUUAUUUAUUGAUUUUCAGUAUUGAGUUGAUAUCCUAGCAGCUUCCAAAGGUGACCAAUGAAUGUUUAUCUGAGGGUUAUUUUUAUUUUUAUUUUUUUUGAGACAGGGACUUGCUCUGUUGCCCAGACUGGAAUUCAGUGGCUCAAUCAUAGCUCAUUGUAGCCACCAAAAGUGUUGGGAUUAUAGGCGUGAGCCACCCAGCCCGGCCACAGUCGUUCUUCUUUCUGAUGCUCAAAUUGCCCCAUCUUUAGCCAAUAGGAACCUCCUGGCCGGGCGCGGUGGCUCAUGCCUGUAACCCCAGCACUUUGGGAGGCCGAGGUGGGUGGAUCACGAGGUCAGGAGAUCGAGACCAUCCUAACACGGUGAAACCCCGUCUCUACUAAAAAUACAAAAAAUUCACCGGGCGUGGUGGCGGGCGCCUGUAGUCUCAGCUACUUUGGGAGUCUGAGGCAGAAUGGCUUGAACCCGGGAGGUGGAGCUUGCAGUGAGCCGAGAUCGCGCCACUGCACUCCAGCCUGGGCGACAGAGCAAGACUCCGUCUCAACAACAACAACAAAAAAAAGAGCCUCCUUCAGAUUGGUGCCAGUGUCCUUUAGACAGAACUCUAGUAGUCUUUUCAGAUUCAACUUGUACAUUUCCUUCCCCAGACUUCAACUGAUCCAUUUUCUAAGGAGUCCUAGUUCCUAAAUGGGUGUUAUUACUAUUUUAUCUCGGUUUAAGUGUUUUACAGUGGGAGAGGUUGGAGGUCUCUAGUACAGGGUAUUGCUGGAAAUGAAAGCCUCCUUUCUCUGCUCCUGUAUUUUCUUCUGGGGCUUCCAUCUCUUCUCAAGCCUUUUCACCUCCUCCAA